GAGAGGCUGCGCUUGGAGCCCAGACUGACGCGCUUCUCUCAUGGUUCCGGGCCGCUGCCCUGCAGAGCCCACCUUACUCUUACUCUCCACAGGCCUGUUGGCCGCGGCGGGCCUUGGCUCCCCUGAGCCUGGUGGGCCUGCAAAGAGCUGCGUCCAGGAGCCGCCCCCAGGGAACAAGCUGCCAGCGGGCCUGGGGAGAACCGCCCGUCCGAUGAGCUCGGCUGAGCGUGCACGCAGUGCCGAAAUCAAGGACGCCUGGAUGCUUUUCGUUGCAGAGUGACAAAGGUUCAACAACAGGAAGAGGAUCAGGGGCCAAGACAAGAAGCUGAAGUUCGGCCUGCCAGGAACCCCGGGCCCCAGCAUCCCACCCAAGGCGCUGCUGCAGGAGUUCCAGCUGCUGCUGAAAGGUGCGGUGCCGCAGGGCCAGAGUGCGGGAUCCUGAGCCCUGCAUGCCAGUCCUUGCGGGGGCCGAUCGCUGUGAGCCUUACUCAGGUCCAGCCGCCUCCAGGGAGGACAAUGUAGACGAGGUGCGGGGCGUGAGGGCGGUGCUGGCCGCACCCCUGGUCCUGAGGCCACGGGAGCCGCGCGAGGAGGCCGCCUUCCACUGACGCCUGCACCGGGACCGGUUGCUGCAGCGGUGCCAGCUGCAGGAGCUCCGCGUCUGCUGCUUCUCCGACGCCAGGGCGCCGCCAGGAUGACAGGUGCAGGAGACUGUGGCUGUGGGCAGAUGUGGUUUCCAGCCCCAGGUCCCCGCGGCCCCUGGCUUCCCAGCGCGCUGUCCUGUGAGCAAGAAGAUGAAAAAAGCCACCCGAUCAACAGGUCAGCUGCCCCGCCUGGCAGCCCAGCCAGACAAGGCAACCGAAGUUCAUCCUCUCUGAGUUGACUUCGUGCGGGCAGCGGGCCGGCGCCCAGGAUGCUGGGGAGCCCUGCGCGCCGGAGGCCGACAAGCCGUGGGGCUCAGAGGCGCCUCAGGGCGAGAAGGCACCCGUCUCCCAGCGCUUUCACCCCCUGGCCUGCCCGGCCCGCGUGGUGUCCCAGUGGCUGCGGCCACGCCAGGCAUUCUGCCCCGCGGCGGCUGCACAGGGACGAGAACUGAGAACCCCUGCUCAACCCCAUCCGGGGUGACUGCCAAAUGCCUAUGCCAGCGGCCCCGAUCUCCCUCCGGUGGAGGAGUGGGGGGAGACACGGCCUGGGGGCCUCAGGCUGGGCGCGCUGGCGAUCCCGAGGCCGACCAGGUCAUGCACCUCCAGUCCGCCUGGGCACCCAAGCUGCAGCCGCCUUCUGUGCGCAGACAGCAGCCUCCAGGCAAUCCCCGAGCCCGCCCGCACUCCCCGCAUCUCAAAACCGGGGCUAGAGGUCCCUGUAGCUGCGGCCAAGCCAGGCGGUCUGCCCUGCGGCGGCUGCACAGGGGCAGGAACCGGCCCUCAGACCCAACCCCGGUGGCUGCAGAGGGCCACUGGCUAGAGGUCCCCAGCUCCAGCAGAGGAGGAGCUGGGCGGGGGCAGGGCCUGGCGGGCUCUCAGGCCAGGUGCACUCGCGAUCUAGAGGCAGCCCAGGCCAUUCUCCACCACCUGGGCGCCCAAGCUGCAGGCGCCCUCUACCUGCUGGCAACAGCUGCCUGGCCACUCCCAAGCUGGCUGGCGCUCCCAAGCCUCGCAGAACCGGGGCUAGAUGUCGCCGUGGCUGCGGCCAAGCCCGGCGGUCUGCCCGGCGGCGGCUGCACCGUGGCUGGAACCGACCCCCCAGUCCCAUCCCCCAUGGCUACGGAGGGCCCCUGUCAGCGGCCCCGAUCUCUCUUUGGAGGAGGAGCGGGGCGGGAGUCACGGCCAGGAGGGCCCUCAGGCCGGAAGGGAUGCACGUCUGCGAUUCCGAGACGUCCCGCGCGAGCCCAGGAGAACCCGCAAGCCAGCAGCGCCUGCGCCCGAGCUGCAGCAGCCCCCUGCAGGCCACGCGGGCUCGGGAGCGGUUUCCGGAGUCCGAGCUGGCGCUGAGCUGCAGGCGCGAGCCUAAAGGCUUAGCCGGGGCCCACGCUGUCUGAGAGAUCGGAGCGUUCAGCUACAGGCACGCGCUUAACGGCUUCGUGGAGCUCACUCGGUCUGAGAGGUCGGAGGCUGCGAGUGUCGCUGCUGAAGGCUGUGGUGGACCAGGC